GUGGGGAAACUGAGGCCCGAAGGGGGCCGACGCCCCGCGGCGGGGUAGCUGCUUGUCCGGGGAGGCCAGUAUCCGCCCGGGUUAAGACUCAGGGCGUCCCCAGGCUGAGCUUCUUAGGGACGGCGUUCGGCCCCCACCUGUCACCACCCUGGCAUUUUCACCCCAGGAGCCUCACUCUAGGAGCGGUUGCUCACGCUGGGCCCUGUGCCUGGAACGCCCUCGUGCCUUCUCUGCCUUCACAGCCCUGCUGGGGGCUUUUGCGUGCUCCCUAGCUCUUCUUACAGGCCUUUCACCGCUGGUUCAGCCUUUGUGGAGCACUUAGAGACCGUGUUCCCAGCACUCCCCACUAUGUGCAGGAGGUGAAGCCUUGAACACACUUGCUGAAGAACGAACAUAAGGCAGGUUCUGGGAUUGACGGGGGCUGCUUUAGAGUGGGUGGUCCCGUAGGCCAGACACUGGAGCUGAAACAUAAAUGAAUUAAAAGGAACCAACUUAGCUUUUCAGUUGUAAGGUGCCAAGGCCCAGGCUUGGAACAAAGUCAAGCACAAUACACUAGUUCGCUGCAGGACUUAACAUCCUGGGUGAUAGUGACUGAUUUGUAACCGCAGUACCCAGCACAGUGCCUGAUACACAAUGUUUGGAAUAUGUGAAAGCACUCUGUAUACUACAAAACAUCCUUUCCCAGUGGGUUUAUUUCCUGGGCCACACACCUUUUGGUUGCUAGGGGGGUGAUAACUAGAAGACGGUCGCCCAACUCCGGAGGGUGAAGCAUAGCGCCUGAAGCCAGAGGGCCUACACGGCAUCUGUAAAAUUCCACCCCAUUUCAGCGCUGGGGUUGUAAACAAAAUUAGUCUCACCCCAAAAUUGCCAAAAGAAGACAGCUUUUUCCACUAGAAGAAACGGGUUAGGGAAUAGAAUCAGGAACCUUCACUCGUUGAGUUUUUUUGACUGAUGUUAGCUGCUUAGGGUUGUAUCCAGUUAAUCAUCAAGACUGGAGAGUUGUCUUGCUAAGGUUUAGGAAGACCAGUGUGAUUCUGUCCAGAUGCCACACUAUCACUAUCUAGAGGUGUGACCUUGGGUAAGUCAACCUUUUUGGACUUUGGUCUGGGUCAGAAGGCUGCAAGGUGCCAUCUGGGGGCAGCUAUCUGCAAAGCCUCUGCUCUGCGCCCGGCGCUGUGCGGGGCCGCUCAGUUUUCAGCAGUGUUUUUGUACCGGCAUUUUGCAGGUGGGAAACAAGCUCAGGGAGGUUGCGUGGCUUUGCCCAAGGUCCCUCAGGUGUGGCUGCUCUCCCUAGCCCCUGUACUCCUCACCAUACCCUGCUGAAUAUGGCCACAGCUUUUUGGGUUUGGAAUCCAAAAAUGACAUAUUUUUCGUAAAGCAAAAGCAAACUUAUUCGAGCUUAGGCAGCAUGAUGGGAUUGUAUUUUGUAGCUAAUCUAAUGGAGACGAUAUAAAUUCUACCUGCAAUAAUAUACCUUUGCAGCACAUUCUUUUAAUACUCUUUCAGCCCCAGCUGUGUCAUGGAGGCCACAAAGGCAAACCGGAUGCGUACUUUGCCCCUCAGUAGUUUAUGAACUAACAGGAGAUGAAACAAGACCCAGAUAACUUCUAGUCAAGGCCAGAAAGCUAAAGAUAGUGAAAAAGAACUGAAUGUAUUUAGAGAAAGGGAGAUUGUUCCUGGCUGAGGACAUCAGAAGCAGCUUUGUUGAAGAAGUGGUAUCUGAACUAGAUUUGAAAGGGUGCGUCUGAGUUGAAAAUGCAGAAGGGGAGAGGCAGGUUCUGGGGCGGUUGGGGGUGCAUUUCAACAACCACAGCAGAAGGCCCAGUGUUCGCUGUGGGGGUGGUGUGGAUCAGCAGCACAGACCAAUGGACACACUUGGGUCAGAUCGAGGCCCCUGUCUCUCCCCAUCCUCCCUCUUCCCCACCCCACAGAAAUUUCCAGUUCCAUCCAACAUGCUGUGCCCCUUUUCAUGCAUCCGUGCAUUUACACAUGGAUGUGUGCCCUUUUUCACCUGGCAAAAAUUCCCAGCCUUCAAAAUGCCCCUCAGAGAUCACAGCUUCUGGGCAGCCCACCACCUCUGGGCUGUUCCUGCCUCUUGAUUGCACCUGUUGUACCAUGAUGACAUUUUUCCUGUCUGCCUCACCUGUCUGCAUUCCUUAGGGAAGCUUGUCUGCCUUCAGAAUCAUCAGUGGAGCUUUUGAAAGGGCAGAUCUUGGGGCCUCACCCCAGGAGAUCCGAUUCAGCAGGUCUGCGGGGACUGAGAUGGAGUCUCACUCUGUUGCCCAGGCUGGAGUGCAGUGGUGCGAUCUCAGCUUACUGCAACCUCCUCCCGGGUUCAAGCGAUUCUCAUGCCUCAGCCUCCUGAGUAGCUGGGACUACAGGAGUGCAUCACCACGCCCAGCUCAUUUUUGUAUUUUUAGUAGAGAUGGGGUUUCACCAUGUUGGCCAGCAACUAGAAGCCAUUUGUGUCAAGGUAACGUCUGGAGAAACAAAAGGUCAGGAAAGGCCAAUGCUCCUACCGACCACAAUCCAGCCCCAAACUGCAAGAAAGAGCCAGCUGCCCCGGGGGAAUUCCUGCCUGGUGGGGCUCCAUAUCGCCAGCCCUCAGCUGCUCAGGGUACAGCCGCUUGUGAGAACCGAGCCACAGUCCUGCUUCCUAAGUGACUUAUGCCAACCUCCUGCUCAGGGGUUUGUACAGAGACCACUGCCAGCCCUCCAGGUGGUCCCUGCAAAGAGAGUCCCAGCCCCCAAGGCUCCAGAUGAACAGGGCUCCAUGUUGACCCCUUUGUCUGCCUCUGACCCGCUGGCAGUAACAUCUCUUUCAUCCAGUUCAGCACAUCCAUUUAUUUCCAACUUGCAUACAAGACAUACUGAGAAACUAAAAAAAUCGUUAAAAGUAAAGACACGUUCUGGACGGGUAUCUCGACCUCCCAAAUAUAAAGCUAAAGAUUAUAAGUUCAUAAAAACAGAGGAUCUGGCGGAUGGUCAUCUGUCAGAUUCUGAUGAUUACUCAGAACUCUGUGUGGAAGAAGAUGAAGAUCAGAGGGAGAGGCACGCACUCUUUGACUUAUCGAGCUGCUCCCUGAGGCCCAAAAGCUUUAAGUGUCAGACUUGUGAAAAGUCAUAUAUAGGGAAGGGGGGACUGGCCCGACAUUUUAAACUUAACCCAGGCCACGGCCAGUUGGACCCCGAGAUGGUGCUGUCUGAGAAAGCCAGUGGAAGCACCCUCCGGGGGUGCACGGAGGAAAGGACGCUCAGCCUGACCUCCCUGGGGCUGUCCAUGCCAGCGGAUCCAUGUGAGGGAGGGGCCCGCUCCUGCUUGGUGACAGAGUCAGCACGCGGUGGCCUGCAGAAUGGUCAGUCUGUAGACGUUGAAGAGACAUUGCCAUCUGAACCAGAAAAUGGAGCUCUUUUGCGAUCAGAGAGAUACCAAGGACCUAGAAGACGCGCAUGCUCAGAGACCCUUGCAGAGUCCCGCACAGCUGUCCUCCAGCAGAGAAGAGCUGCUCAGCUACCUGGUGGCCCUGCUGCGGCAGGGGAGCAGAGGGCGUCGCCAAGCAAAGCCAGGCUCAAGGAGUUCCUCCAGCAGUGUGACCGGGAGGAUCUGGUGGAAUUGGCUCUGCCUCAGCUGGCUCAGGUUGUGACCGUGUAUGAGUUUCUUCUGAUGAAGGUUGAAAAAGAUCAUCUAGCAAAGCCUUUUUUCCCAGCUAUAUAUAAGGAAUUUGAAGAGUUGCAUAAAAUGGUUAAGAAAAUGUGCCAAGAUUACCUCAGUAGUUCUGGUCUGUGUUCCCAGGAGACCCUGGAAAUAAACAAUGAUAAGGUUGCUGAGUCAUUAGGAAUCACAGAAUUCCUACGGAAGAAAGAAAUACACCCAGACAACCUUGGACCCAAGCACCUCAGCCGAGACAUGGAUGGGGAGCAGCUAGAGGGAGCUAGCAGCGAGAAGAGGGAACGUGAGGCUGCGGAGGAGGGACUGGCCUCAGUGAAAAGGCCCAGAAGAGAAGCCCUGUCCAACGAUACCACUGAAUCUCUUGCUGCCAACAGCAGAGGCCGGGAGAAGCCCAGGCCCUUGCAUGCUUUGGCCGCUGGUUUUUCCCCUCCAGUAAAUGUGACUGUCUCUCCCCGUUCUGAAGAAAGCCAUACAACGACGGUUUCUGGUGGCAAUGGGAGCGUGUUCCAGGCGGGCCCGCAGCUUCAGGCACUGGCUAACUUAGAAGCCAGGAGGGGGUCUAUAGGUGCUGCUCUCUCAUCCCGGGAUGUCAGUGGGCUGCCUGUUUAUGCUCAGUCAGGAGAGCCUAGGAGGCUGACCCAGGCACAGGUGGCAGCGUUUCCUGGAGAGAAUGCUUUGGAACACUCUUCAGACCAGGACACCUGGGACAGCCUGAGGAGCCCGGGUUUCUGCAGCCCUUUGUCAUCUGGUGGUGGAGCAGAGUCCCUGCCGCCUGGGGGGCCUGGACAUGCAGAGGCAGGACACCUCGGCAAGGUUUGUGACUUCCACCUGAACCACCAGCAGCCCAGCCCCACCAGCGUCCUGCCUACAGAGGUGGCAGCCCCUCCGCUUGAGAAAAUUUUGUCUGUGGAUAGCGUGGCAGUGGACUGUGCCUACAGGACUGUGCCCAAGCCAGGGCCUCAGCCUGGCCCACAUGGAUCACUAUUGACUGAAGGGUGUCUCAGAAGCCUUUCGGGGGACUUGAACCGGUUCCCCUGUGGGAUGGAGGUGCACUCUGGCCAGAGAGAACUGGAGAGCGUGGUUGCUGUCGGCGAAGCCAUGGCUUUUGAAAUUUCCAAUGGGAGCCAUGAGUUACUGUCUCAGGGACAGAAGCAGAUUUUUAUUCAGACUUCCGAUGGGCUUAUCUUGUCCCCUCCAGGUACAAUAGUGUCUCAGGAGGAGGACAUUGUCACAGUGACUGAUGCAGAGGGGCGUGCCUGCGGAUGGGCCCGCUAGAAGGAGUUCCUCUAGAAGCUGUGGAGUCGGUCGUCACCGUGGAGCCAGAGCCCUCACAGUGAAGUGGAGUCAGAUCCUAGAUUCGUCUGAUUUUAUCCAGAGAAGGUCUAUGGCAAGCAAUGUAUAUUUUUCUAAUGUGAAUAUUGCACAGAUGAACCUUUUAUUUAUAAAGAAUAAUGUCUUUCUGC